GCAGAGGAAGAAGCUGGAGACUUGGUCCAGCCGGGCAUCAGCUUUCCGGGGCCGGCAGAGGAGGAUCUAGACCCGCAGUACUCAUGGUCGCCCACGCAGCACUUCAAUGAGGAGCGCUACUCGCCCGCGCCCAGGAGCAUGAAGGGCCUUUCCGGAAGUCGGACCCAGCCGCCGCUGUGUUCCGGGCACACGUGUGGUCUGGCGCCCCCGGAGGACUGCGAGCACCUGCACCACGGGCCCGACGCGCGGCCGCCCUACCUGCUGAGCCCCGCCGACAGCUGCCCCGGGGGGCGCCACCGCUGCUCGCCGCGCAGCUCGGUGCACUCGGAGUGCGUGAUGAUGCCGGUGGUGCUGGGCGACCACGUGUCCAGCAGCACCUUCCCGCGGAUGCACUACAGCUCGCACUACGACACGCGCGACGACUGCGCUGUGGCCCACGCGGGCGCCAAGAUCAACCGCAUCCCGGCCAACCUGCUGGACCAGUUCGAGAAGCAGCUGCCGCUGCACCGGGACGGCUUCCACACGCUGCAGUACCAGAGGACGUCCGCGGCCGCCGAGCAGCGCAGCGAGAGCCCCGGGCGGAUCCGCCACCUGGUACACUCCGUGCAGAAGCUCUUCACCAAGUCGCACUCGCUGGAGGGCUCCUCCAAAAGCAACGCCAACGGCACCAAGGCGGACGGCCGGGCGGACGACCACCACCACGCCCACCACGCCAAGCACAGCAAGAGGAGCAAGAGCAAGGAGCGCAAGCCGGAGGGCAAGCCCCGGCCCGGCAUGAGCAGCUGGUGGAGCUCGGACGACAACCUGGACAGCGACAGCACCUAUCGGACGCCCAGCGUGCUCAACCGGCACCACCUGGGCCCCGUGGCCCACUGCUACCCCGACGCGCUGCAGAGCCCCUUCGGGGACCUGUCCCUCAAGACCUCCAAGAGCAACAACGACGUCAAGUGCUCGGCCUGUGAGGGGUUGGCGCUGACGCCCGACGCCAAGUACCUGAAGCGCAGCUCCUGGUCUACGCUGACGGUCAGCCAGGCCAAGGAGGCCUACCGCAAGAGCUCGCUGAACCUGGACAAGCCGCUGCUGCACCAGGACGCCAAGCCCGCCCUGAGGCCGUGCCACUACCUCCAGGUACCUCAGGAUGAGUGGGGAGGGUACCCCACCGGUGGCAAAGAUGAGGAGAUUCCCUGCAGGAGAAUGAGAAGUGGGAGUUACAUUAAAGCCAUGGGGGACGAGGAGAGCGGAGAGUCAGACUCCAGCCCCAAGACAUCACCAAAGUCGGCAAUCCUACCAGAGCCGCUGCUGAAGUCCAUCGGACAGAGACCGCUUGGAGAGCACCAGAAUAGUUAAGAAUGAAGAACCUGAGAAAAUCUCAAAGACAGAUAAAAACUGCCACAAACUUAGUGUCUUA